CUUUCCCUGGUGUGAUUCCGUCCUGCGCGGUUGUUCUCUGGAGCAGCGUUCUUUUAUCUCCGUCCGCCUUCUCUCCUACCUAAGUGCGUGCCGCCACCCGAUGGAAGAUUCGAUGGACAUGGACAUGAGCCCCCUGAGGCCCCAGAACUAUCUUUUCGGUUGUGAACUAAAGGCCGACAAAGAUUAUCACUUUAAGGUGGAUAAUGAUGAAAAUGAGCACCAGUUAUCUUUAAGAACGGUCAGUUUAGGGGCUGGUGCAAAGGAUGAGUUGCACAUUGUUGAAGCAGAGGCAAUGAAUUACGAAGGCAGUCCAAUUAAAGUAACACUGGCAACUUUGAAAAUGUCUGUACAGCCAACGGUUUCCCUUGGGGGCUUUGAAAUAACACCACCAGUGGUCUUAAGGUUGAAGUGUGGUUCAGGGCCAGUGCAUAUUAGUGGACAGCACUUAGUAGCUGUGGAGGAAGAUGCAGAGUCAGAAGAUGAAGAGGAGGAGGAUGUGAAACUCUUAAGUAUAUCUGGAAAGCGGUCUGCCCCUGGAGGUGGUAGCAAGGUUCCACAGAAAAAAGUAAAACUUGCUGCUGAUGAAGAUGAUGACGAUGAUGAUGAAGAGGAUGAUGAUGAAGAUGAUGAUGAUGAUGAUUUUGAUGAUGAGGAAGCUGAAGAAAAAGCGCCAGUGAAGAAAUCUAUACGAGAUACUCCAGCCAAAAAUGCACAAAAGUCAAAUCAGAAUGGAAAAGACUCAAAACCAUCAUCAACACCAAGAUCAAAAGGACAAGAAUCCUUCAAGAAACAGGAAAAAACUCCUAAAACACCAAAAGGACCUAGUUCUGUAGAAGACAUUAAAGCAAAAAUGCAAGCAAGUAUAGAAAAAGCGCAUUGAACAGUCCUGGGCACUACAUGUAAAUUAAGCCCAAAGAUGGGGAGAAAGGAAAAGGAGAGACAAAUAUAGUCCAUACUGAGUGUCAUCAACAAUCCAGACUGAAGUCUUCUAUUUUAAUCUCAAUCCCCUUUUCUGAUUUGCCACCCAUGCCUCUUCAGGCUGGAAACAAUCUCUUGGUUCCCUAAAGCACUUUCUUCUGACUGCUGUGAUUCAGUGAACCUUGCCCUUUGCUUUCUAUUACUUGUGCAUUUGCCUCACCUGACAAUGUUUUAAAUCGCCUUUGUAUCUCCUUAGCUGCUCAAUAAAUAUUUGAAUGCAUCAAUUAAGAAUGUAUGUGACAAUAAUUUUGAAAUGGAAAUUGUGAGGUUUAUUUUACUAGGUUAUUGGAGGCAGUUAAGUUUCUUAAUGCUAUACCUGAUUCUGCCAAAGUCCCUUGGACAUUUGAAAACCUUUUCAAUCUUUUAAAAAUGCAUAAAAGAUACUUAGAGGGAAAGGUAUUAAUUAAAUUUAGUAAAAACAAAUAUAUUCAAUGCUUUAAAUUCCAAAGUAGUGAUAAAUACAAACAUUUCAAGAUAUUUGCAAUAGUAAUGUUUUGAAAUUUUGGUUACAAAGUCACAGGUCUUGCCAAUACUGUUGUAGUUUCUUGCCUAUAUCCGUAAUUUGAAGGAAAUGGUGAGAGUGAUUAGAGAAGUGUAAUUACUGUAAUUUUUUCCCCUAUUG